AAUAUGACAGAUACCUAGCAUCUAGCAAAAUAAUGGCAGCUGCUUACCUUGACCCCAACUUGAAUCACACACCAAAUUCGAGUACUAAGACUCACCUGGGUACUGGUAUGGAACGUUCUCCUGGUGCAAUGGAGCGAGUAUUAAAGGUCUUUCAUUAUUUUGAAAGCAAUAGUGAGCCAACCACCUGGGCCAGUAUUAUCAGGCAUGGAGAUGCUACUGAUGUCAGGGAUGGAAAGUAUCAUCUAGGAAGAAAGCUAGAAAGGAAAGCUUUAAGAAAAAGCAUAAAAGCCAUGUUAAAGAGGAGAACCUAAGCUAACAGAGCACGAGGAAGAAAAAAUUUUGAAUUCAAAAUCCUGAGAGAUAGUGAUUGAGGUAGUGAUUUCCCAUAGGUAGAAUGUUGGCUCCUAAAGAUGCCUACAUCCUAAUCCCCAGAACCUGUGCAGAUGUCCCCUUACGUGGCCAGAGGGACUUGUAGGCGUGAUGAAGGCUACAGACCUUAAGGUGGGGAGAUCAUGAGUCCUUCACUGCAGCAGGCCUUUUCUUAACCGUGGUCAGUGGGAGGUGAAUAUGAAAGAAGGAUCAGAUGCAACGUUGAGGGAAGAAGACGACCAUGAGCCAAGGAGUGCAGUGCCCUGUAGAAGCUGGAAAAGACAAGCUAAGAGCCUCCAGAAAACAGCACAUCCCUGCUGACGUCUUUAUUUUAGGCCAGUGAGACCCAUUUCAUACUUGUGAUCUACAAAACUAAAAGAUAAUGCACUUGUUGUGUUUUAAGCUCCCAAGUUUGUGGUGAUUUAUUACAGAGGUAAUAGGGAACUAAUACAGUGACUGUGGACCACCAAGAUAAAAAAGUACAUUCUUUGUCUUGGAAGACUUUUAGAAGGACUCCUAGUUUAUGACUGGACCAAGAGGAGGAAACGUACUAGGUGUUGGAGAACAGGAUUUGAAUUUCUGGAUCUUUCUUUUUGAUAACCCAAUGAUGAAAGCCUCCAAGAAGAAUGGUAGGAAUCCCUUGGUUUUCUAAAGCUGAAGAGUAUCUGAAAGAGAAACACAAUGAGAAAAAGAAACACUAUACUAUAGAAGAAUCAGUAAUGAUGAUUAUAUUUGGUAAUUCUUAGGAAGCAGUAAGGAGAUAAACAGUGUCAACAAUGUGUGUUGCUUCAGAUAUCUCUUCUAGUAAUAAAUCUGAAAAUUAAGUGUGAGACUAUAGCUAAAAAUAUAAAAUAUCCCUUUUUGUCCCCUCCUCCCCACAAACCACUUAAUACUCAUUUGCACAUGUUCAUUGUCAUGUCUUUCUCCUGUGAGACUCUUUAAGACUUCUGAGGGUCAGAAUUGCAUCUUAACCGUUAUUGUGUCACUAGCAUCAUGCAUGUAGUAGGCACUUCAGAUGUUCAUGAAUAAAUGAAUGAACAGUUUAUGAAAGAAUGAACAUGGAGGAAAGAGUCACAUGACCUAUUUCGAACAGUGGUGAAGGUCAUUUGUUUGAAAGUACUGUCUAAAAGGGCAUCAUUCAGAAGAUAGUGGACAGUCACAAAGUAAAGCAUGUGGCCUGCUAUGGAUUCCGCCUCAGUCACCUGCGGUCAGAGGAGGUUCACUGGCUUCACGUGGAUAUGGGCGUCUCCAGUGUGAGGGAGAAGUAUGAGCUUGCUCACCCACCAGAGGAGUGGAAAUAUGAAUUGAGAAUUCGUUAUUUGCCAAAAGGAUUUCUAAACCAGUUUACUGAAGAUAAGCCAACUUUGAAUUUCUUCUAUCAACAGGUGAAGAGCGAUUAUAUGUUAGAGAUAGCUGAUCAAGUGGACCAGGAAAUUGCUUUGAAGUUGGGUUGUCUAGAAAUACGGCGAUCAUACUGGGAGAUGCGGGGCAAUGCACUAGAAAAGAAGUCUAACUAUGAAGUAUUAGAAAAAGAUGUUGGUUUAAAGCGAUUUUUUCCUAAGAGUUUACUGGAUUCUGUCAAGGCCAAAACACUAAGAAAACUGAUCCAACAAACAUUUAGACAAUUUGCCAACCUUAAUAGAGAAGAAAGUAUUCUGAAAUUCUUUGAGAUCCUGUCUCCAGUCUACAGAUUUGAUAAGGAAUGCUUCAAGUGUGCUCUUGGUUCAAGCUGGAUUAUUUCAGUGGAACUGGCAAUCGGCCCAGAAGAAGGAAUCAGUUACCUAACGGACAAGGGCUGCAAUCCCACACAUCUUGCUGACUUCACUCAAGUGCAAACCAUUCAGUAUUCAAACAGUGAAGACAAGGACAGAAAAGGAAUGCUACAACUAAAAAUAGCAGGUGCACCCGAGCCUCUGACAGUGACGGCACCAUCCCUAACCAUUGCGGAGAAUAUGGCUGACCUAAUAGAUGGGUACUGCCGGCUGGUGAAUGGAACCUCGCAGUCAUUUAUCAUCAGACCUCAGAAAGAAGGUGAACGGGCUUUGCCAUCAAUACCAAAGUUGGCCAACAGCGAAAAGCAAGGCAUGCGGACACACGCCGUCUCUGUGUCAGGAGUCAGUCACUGCCAACAUAAAGUUAAGAAAGCUAGGCGCUUUCUCCCUUUGGUCUUCUGUUCCCAUGAUCCUCCUUCUACGGAUGAAAUUAGUGGGGACGAAACAGAUGAUUAUGCUGAGAUUAUAGAUGAAGAAGAUACUUACACCAUGCCCUCAAAAAGCUAUGGAAUAGAUGAAGCCAGGGAUUAUGAGAUUCAAAGAGAAAGAAUAGAACUUGGACGAUGUAUUGGAGAAGGCCAAUUUGGAGAUGUACAUCAAGGCAUUUAUAUGAGUCCAGAGAAUCCAGCUUUGGCGGUUGCAAUUAAAACAUGUAAAAACUGUACUUCGGACAGCGUGAGAGAGAAAUUUCUUCAAGAAGCCUUAACAAUGCGUCAGUUUGACCAUCCUCAUAUUGUGAAGCUGAUUGGAGUCAUCACAGAGAAUCCUGUCUGGAUAAUCAUGGAGCUGUGCACACUUGGAGAGCUGAGGUCAUUUUUGCAAGUAAGGAAAUACAGUUUGGAUCUAGCAUCUUUGAUCCUGUAUGCCUAUCAGCUUAGUACAGCUCUUGCAUAUCUAGAGAGCAAAAGAUUUGUACACAGGGACAUUGCUGCUCGGAAUGUUCUGGUGUCCUCAAAUGAUUGUGUAAAAUUAGGAGACUUUGGAUUAUCCCGAUAUAUGGAAGAUAGUACUUACUACAAAGCUUCCAAAGGAAAAUUGCCUAUUAAAUGGAUGGCUCCAGAGUCAAUCAAUUUUCGACGUUUUACCUCAGCUAGUGACGUAUGGAUGUUUGGUGUGUGUAUGUGGGAGAUACUGAUGCAUGGUGUGAAGCCUUUUCAAGGAGUGAAGAACAAUGAUGUAAUCGGUCGAAUUGAAAAUGGGGAAAGAUUACCAAUGCCUCCAAAUUGUCCUCCUACCCUCUACAGCCUUAUGACGAAAUGCUGGGCCUAUGACCCCAGCAGGCGGCCCAGGUUUACUGAACUUAAAGCUCAGCUCAGCACAAUCCUGGAGGAAGAGAAGGCUCAGCAAGAAGAGCGCAUGAGGAUGGAGUCCAGAAGACAGGCCACAGUGUCCUGGGACUCCGGAGGGUCUGAUGAAGCACCGCCCAAGCCCAGCAGACCGGGUUAUCCCAGUCCGAGGUCCAGCGAAGGAUUUUAUCCCAGCCCACAGCACAUGGUACAAACCAAUCAUUACCAGGUUUCUGGCUACCCUGGUUCACAUGGAAUCACAGCCAUGGCUGGCAGCAUCUAUCCAGGUCAGGCAUCUCUUUUGGACCAAACAGAUUCAUGGAAUCAUAGACCUCAGGAGAUAGCAAUGUGGCAGCCCAAUGUGGAGGACUCUACAGUAUUGGACCUGCGAGGGAUUGGGCAAGUGUUGCCAACCCAUCUGAUGGAAGAGCGUCUAAUCCGACAGCAACAGGAAAUGGAAGAAGAUCAGCGCUGGCUGGAAAAAGAGGAAAGAUUUCUGAAACCUGAUGUGAGACUCUCUCGAGGCAGUAUUGACAGGGAGGAUGGAAGUCUUCAGGGUCCGAUUGGAAACCAACAUAUAUAUCAGCCUGUGGGUAAACCAGAUCCUGCAGCUCCACCAAAGAAACCGCCUCGCCCUGGAGCUCCCGGUCAUCUGGGAAGCCUUGCCAGCCUCAGCAGCCCUGCUGACAGCUACAACGAGGGUGUCAAGCCAUGGAGGCUUCAGCCCCAGGAAAUCAGCCCCCCUCCUACUGCCAACCUGGACCGGUCGAAUGAUAAGGUGUACGAGAAUGUGACGGGCCUGGUGAAAGCUGUCAUCGAGAUGUCCAGUAAAAUCCAGCCAGCCCCACCAGAGGAGUAUGUCCCUAUGGUGAAGGAAGUCGGCUUGGCCCUGAGGACAUUAUUGGCCACUGUGGAUGAGACCAUUCCCCUCCUACCAGCCAGCACCCACCGAGAGAUUGAGAUGGCACAGAAGCUAUUGAACUCUGACCUGGGUGAGCUCAUCAACAAGAUGAAACUGGCCCAGCAGUAUGUCAUGACCAGCCUCCAGCAAGAGUACAAAAAGCAAAUGCUGACUGCUGCUCACGCCCUGGCUGUGGAUGCCAAAAACUUACUCGAUGUCAUUGACCAAGCAAGACUGAAAAUGCUUGGGCAGACGAGACCACACUGAGCCUCCCCUAGGAGCACGUCUUGCUACCCUCUUUUGAAGAUGUUCUCUAGCCUUCCACCAGCAGCGAGGAAUUAACCCUGUGUCCUCAGUCGCCAGCACUUACAGCUCCAACUUUUUUGAAUGACCAUCUGGUUGAAAAAUCUUUCUCAUAUAAGUUUAACCACACUUUGAUUUGGGUUCAUUUUUUGUUUUGUUUUUUUCAAUCAUGAUAUUCAGAAAAAUCCAGGAUCCAAAAUGUGGCGUUUUUCUAAGAAUGAAAAUUAUAUGUAAGCUUUUAAGCAUCAUGAAGAACAAUUUAUGUUCACAUUAAGAUACGUUCUAAAGGGGGAUGGCCAAGGGGUGACAUCUUAAUUCCUAAACUACCUUAGCUGCAUAGUGGAAGAGGAGAGCAUGAAGCAAAGAAUUCCAGGAAACCCAAGAGGCUGAGAAUUCUUUUGUCUACCAUAGAAUUAUUAUCCAGACUGGAAUUUUUGUUUGUUAGAACACCCUUCAGUUGCAAUAUGCUAAUCCCACUUUACAAAGAAUAUAAAAGCUAUAUUUUGAAGACUUGAGUUAUUUCAGAAAAAACUACAGCCCUUUUUGUCUUACCUGCCUUUUACUUUCGUGUGGAUAUGUGAAGCAUUGGGUCGGGAACUAGCUGUAGAACACAACUAAAAACUCAUGUCUUUUUUCACAGAAUAAUGUGCCAGUUUUUUGUAGCAAUGUUAUUUCUCUUGGAAGCAGAAAUGCUUUGUACCAGAGCACCUCCAAACUGCAUUGAGGAGAAGUUCCAGAACCAUCCCCUUUUUCCAUUUUUAUAUAAUUUAUAAAGAAAGAUUAAAGCCAUGUUGACUAUUUUACAGCCACUGGAGUUAACUAACCCUUCCUUGUAUCUGUCUUCCCAGGAGAGAAUGAAGCAAAACAGGAAUUUGGUUUUCUUUUGAUGUCCAGUUACACCAUCCAUUCUGUUAAUUUUGAAAAAAUAUACCCUCCCUUUAGUUUGUUGGGGGAUAUAAAUUAUUCUCAGGAAGAAUAUAAUGAACUGUACAGUUACUUUGACCUAUUAAAAAGGUGUUACCAGUAAAGUUCUUGUUGUAAUAUCCUUUCUUUUGGUUCUGUUUCUUCAGAUGGCUUUUCAGGUGACUUGUCAGAUAAGAUAACAUACAAGAGAGUUCCCAAUAAUUAUCAGGAAGCCUCUCACUAAUUAGUUUCUUUUUUUUUAUUUAAUCUUCUAAACAAGUCAAGGAUGUUACCACAGAAGGGUAGCGUGGCGUAAGUUAACCUUUUCAUUCCAUCGUCACCUAUUAAAUGCAGAGCUCAGGAUGGAAGUAGCAAUGGUCUUCAAUGAAAGAACCUUCCCCUGCGCAGGGUCUCACUAUUCCGCUAACUCGGACUCAAAGCAUAAUUCACUUGUCAAGGAAAUUGUUAGCAUUUCCCAGGCCCACCCUAGUCUUGCUAGAAUCUCUGUGAGCCACAGAGCAGGGAGCAAAUAGAACUGAGAUCUCCAGCACUAGGGACUCAGACUCCAAAGGGAGGGAUUUGAGUGAAUUUUUUCCAGGUAAAUACAUGCUCUUAUGUGCAAAAGCA